AGUGCUUUCGCUUCAUCCUAGAGGCUAAAUGGGCUCCCCUGGACUCGCCUGGCAGAACUAACCACCUAGAAGAACGUUAUUGUAAGGGGGAAAUGCAAACAGGGUGAAGACAAGAGGCAUAGGUGAUGGACACUAAAACAAAGACCGAAGUUCAUGUUUGGAGAGAUGGAGUAACCUGCCACAGGUCACAAAACUAGUCACUGGCAUGGCCACAAUCUGAAUUUGGGACUGUUAGACUGAGAAGCCCAAGCUAAUUCUUGAUACGCUCACUGCCUGGGACAUUUCACACGGUAGAUCUGAGCUUUCUCGCAUCUGAGACUAAAAGGAAAAUGUAGUCCUUAACAGACAGCAGAAGGAAACAGAUUAUUAGCAAAAAGAACUGCUUUCCUAGCAGGAAACCAGAGAAGGAGUUAUUUCAUGCCCAACAUGUGUAGCACCAGUGGGUGUGACCUGGAAGAAAUCCCCCUAGAUGAUGAUGACCUAAACACCAUAGAAUUCAAAAUCCUCGCCUACUACACCAGACAUCAUGUCUUCAAGAGCACCCCUGCUCUCUUCUCACCAAAGCUGCUGAGAACAAGAAGUUUGUCCCAGAGGGGCCUGGGGAAUUGUUCAGCAAAUGAGUCAUGGACAGAGGUGUCAUGGCCUUGCAGAAAUUCCCAAUCCAGUGAGAAGGCCAUAAACCUUGGCAAGAAAAAGUCUUCUUGGAAAGCAUUCUUUGGAGUAGUGGAGAAGGAAGAUUCGCAGAGCACGCCUGCCAAGGUCUCUGCUCAGGGUCAAAGGACGUUGGAAUACCAAGAUUCGCACAGCCAGCAGUGGUCCAGGUGUCUUUCUAACGUGGAGCAGUGCUUGGAGCAUGAAGCUGUGGACCCCAAAGUCAUUUCCAUUGCCAACCGAGUAGCUGAAAUUGUUUACUCCUGGCCACCACCACAAGCGACCCAGGCAGGAGGCUUCAAGUCCAAAGAGAUUUUUGUAACUGAGGGUCUCUCCUUCCAGCUCCAAGGCCACGUGCCUGUAGCUUCAAGUUCUAAGAAAGAUGAAGAAGAACAAAUACUAGCCAAAAUUGUUGAGCUGCUGAAAUAUUCAGGAGAUCAGUUGGAAAGAAAGCUGAAGAAAGAUAAGGCUUUGAUGGGCCACUUCCAGGAUGGGCUGUCCUACUCUGUUUUCAAGACCAUCACAGACCAGGUCCUAAUGGGUGUGGACCCCAGGGGAGAAUCAGAGGUCAAAGCUCAGGGCUUUAAGGCUGCCCUUGUAAUAGACGUCACGGCCAAGCUCACAGCUAUUGACAACCACCCGAUGAACAGGGUCCUGGGCUUUGGCACCAAGUACCUGAAAGAGAACUUCUCGCCAUGGAUCCAGCAGCACGGUGGAUGGGAAAAAAUACUUGGGAUAUCACAUGAAGAAGUAGACUGAAAUAUCAGAUUUGUCAUCAGGAAUACUCUUUGUCUACUGUGGUCCUGUGCACGUUGGCCUCAGAUGGACUACAGGAGAUUACAACGUACAAGGCAGAUGGAGCAUUGACGUUUUCAAAACCAUUAUUCCUGUGACUGGAGAGGCAUCAGGAGAGGUCUCGUUCGUCUCCAGCUCAUAAAAUGUAGCAGCAUCAUCCUUGACAGUGAUGUUUUUCAGGCCCUCCAUUGAGAACCUGAGGAAAUCUGUAAAGAUAAGUGGUGAUGUUGUUUCAAACGUUCAGAACAGAUACCAUCAUCCUGCCUUUGUUAGCUGCUGUAGGGAAAGUGCGUUACAGAUGUCUGCUGACCUCACAAGAGUGAAAAGAUAAACUGUGCAUGUGUUUCCACUUCCGUUUCUAGUACUAUUUAUUUUUAAACUACACUUGGGGUGGCCUAAUACCUAGGAAGAUGUUGCUAUUCACGUUAGUAAACAGCCUAAAGAAACUCUUAGGUUUACUGCUACAUCCAUUUGUUUGGAGAGGUAACUGUUGUCUGUGCCUUUUUGAAAAACUUCCAUUUGGUACAAAAUUUUUACUCCAACACCCCCUCAACCCUUUUCUCAGGGACCACACCUCUUCUUCCCAAGGUCCCUGGGACUUCCUCAUUCUUUGUGGUAGUACAAUGAUUGGUAGCAGGUAAAAUAAAUACAUAGAAAGACUACUGUCAAAA